CAUCUUGGUCCUGCCCUGACAGAUUCUCCUAUCGGGGUCACAGGGACGCUAAGAUUGCUACCUGGACUUUCGUUGACCAUGCUGUCCCGGGUGGUACUUUCCGCCGCCGCCACAGCGGCCCCCUCUCUGAAGAAUGCAGCCUUCCUAGGUCCAGGGGUAUUGCAGGCAACAAGGACCUUUCAUACAGGGCAGCCACACCUUGUCCCUGUACCACCUCUUCCUGAAUACGGAGGAAAAGUUCGUUAUGGACUGAUCCCUGAGGAAUUCUUCCAGUUUCUUUAUCCUAAAACUGGUGUAACAGGACCCUAUGUACUCGGAACUGGGCUUAUCUUGUACGCUUUAUCCAAAGAAAUAUAUGUGAUUAGCGCAGAGACCUUCACUGCCCUAUCAGUACUAGGUGUAAUGGUCUAUGGAAUUAAAAAAUAUGGUCCCUUUGUUGCAGACUUUGCUGAUAAACUCAAUGAGCAAAAACUUGCCCAACUAGAAGAGGCGAAGCAGGCUUCCAUCCAACACAUCCAGAAUGCAAUUGAUACGGAGAAGUCACAACAGGCACUGGUUCAGAAGCGCCAUUACCUUUUUGAUGUGCAAAGGAAUAACAUUGCUAUGGCUUUGGAAGUUACUUACCGGGAACGACUGUAUAGAGUAUAUAAGGAAGUAAAGAAUCGCCUGGACUAUCAUAUAUCUGUGCAGAACAUGAUGCGUCGAAAGGAACAAGAACACAUGAUAAAUUGGGUGGAGAAGCACGUGGUGCAAAGCAUCUCCACACAGCAGGAAAAGGAGACAAUUGCCAAGUGCAUUGCGGACCUAAAGCUGCUGGCAAAGAAGGCUCAAGCACAGCCAGUUAUGUAAAUGUAUCUAUCCCAAUUGAGACAGCUAGAAACAGUUGACUGACUAAAUGGAAACUAGUCUAUUUGACAAAGUCUUUCUGUGUUGGUGUCUACUGAAGUUAUAGUUUACCCUUCCUAAAAAUGAAAAGUUUGUUUCAUAUAGUGAGAGAACGAAAUCUCUAUCGGCCAGUCAGAUGUUUCUCAUCCUUCUUGCUCUGCCUUUGAGUUGUUCCGUGAUCACUUCUGAAUAAGCAGUUUGCCUUUAUAAAAACUUGCUGCCUGACUAAAGAUUAACAGGUUAUAGUUUAAAUUUGUAAUUAAUUCUACCAUCUUGCAAUAAAGUGACAAUUGAAUGAAACAGGGUUUUUCAAGUUGUAUAAUUCUCUGAAAUACUCAGCUUUUGUCAUAUGGGUAAAAAUUAAAGAUGUCAUUGAACUACUGUCUUGUUUAUGAGACCAUUCAGUGGUGAACUGUUUCUGGCUGAUAGGUUAUGAGAUAUGUAAAGCUUUCUAGUACUCUUAAAAUAACUAAAUGGAGUAUUAUAUAUCAAUUCAUAUCAUUGACUUUAUUAUUUUAGUAGUAUGCCUAUAGAAAAUAUUAUGGACUCAGAGUGUCAUAAAAUCACUCUUAAGAAUCCAUGCAGCAGGCCAGGCACAGUGGCUCACACCUGUAAUGCCUGCACUUUGGAAGGCCGAGACAGGCGGAUCACUUGAGGUCAGGAGUUUGAAACCAGCCAGGCCAACACAGUGAAACCCUGUCUCUACUAAAAAUACAAAAGGUUAGCCGGGCAUGGUGGCAGGCGCCUGUAAUCCCAGCUACUCAGGAGGCUGAGGCAGGAGAAUUGCUUGAACGCAGGAGGCAAAGGUUGCAGUGAGCUGAGAUCACGCCACUGCACUCCAGCCUGGGCAACAGACCUCGACUCCAUCUAGAAAAAAAAAAAAAAAAAUCCAGCAGACACCUAUCAGGAACAUAGAAAAUAACAAGUGUUGGCAAGGAAGUGGAGAAGUUGGAACACUUGUGCACUGUUCGUAGAAAUAUGAAAUGGUACAGCCAUUAUGGAAAAGUGUGGUGAUUCCUCAUAAAAUUAAAAUGGAAAUACCAUGAUCCAGCAAUCCCAGUCGACAUAUAUACUCAAAAAAAUUAAAAGCAGGGUCUUGAAGAGAUACUUGUGUUCCAUGGUGAUAGCAGCCAUUGUUCACAAUAGCUAAAACAUAGAAGCAGCCCAAUCGGCCAUCAGUAGAUGAAUGGAUAAGCAAAAUGUAGUAUAUCCAUGCAAUGGAAUAUUAUUCCACUUCAAGGAAGAAAAUUCUGACACUGGCUACAGCAUGAAUGAACCUUGAGGACGUUAUGCAGUUUUACAGGAUGAGUUAUGGAGCUGGAUAGUGGUGAUGGUGGCACAUUAAGGAUGUAUUUAAUACUGUUCUUAAAUGGUACACUUAAAAAUGGUAAAUUUUAUGUGUAUUUUACAAUCUUUUUUUAAAUUGAAGAAAAAUCCUGUAGAUAAAUUAGAAAAUUCUUCCCUUCAUAGGUUUAUCUGCAUUUGAUUCUCCCAUACUUGUACAAGGAUUUAUUUGUAUUCAAAUGGACAAAUUACGCAAUAGGAAAUAUUUGAAAAUAUUUAUCAUGGGUAAUUGCUAUUUUCAUUGACUUCCUAAGAUUUUAUGUAAUAAUCAUUUGAGUCAAUAUUGGUAGCUAAUGUACUAAUCUAAUAUUGAAAUCAGAUUGAUAUCUUUGUUACUUAAAGAUAAUUUGAUUGGAUCAGCAGUUAUUUCAAAUUGAUUAAACAAAAAAUUAUAAAACA